ACACUUGCCUGUGGUGUCAGCAAGCACUGUCGACUUCUUCCUCUGGUGAAGUGGGUUUACUUGAACUUGAAGGAAAGAAAAAAAAAUGUCUCCACUUCUGAGAAGCAUCUGUGACAUCACUGAAAUUUUCAAUCAGUAUGUCUCUCAUGAUUGUGAUGGAGCAGCAUUAACUAAGAAAGACCUGAAGAACCUCCUUGAAAGGGAAUUUGGAGCUGUGCUUCGGAGACCACAUGACCCUAAGACGGUAGAUCUGAUCCUGGAACUUCUGGAUCUUGACAGUAAUGGGCGUGUCGAUUUCAACGAAUUCCUCCUAUUUAUUUUCAAAGUGGCUCAAGCUUGUUACUAUGCUCUCGGCCAGGCCACGGGACUGGAUGAGGAGAAGCGAGCCCGGUGUGACGGAAAGGAGAGCCUGUUACAAGAUCGCAGGCAAGAAGAAGACCAAAGGAGAUUCGAGCCCCGGGACAGACAACUGGAAGAAGAACCUGGGCAACGACGCAGGCAGAAGAGGCAGGAACAGGAGAGGGAGCUAGCUGAGGGAGAGGAGCAAAGUGAGAAACAAGAGCGACUUGAACAGCGCGACAGGCAGCGCCGCGACGAGGAGCUGUGGCGGCAAAGGCAAGAAUGGCAAGAACGGGAAGAGCGCCGUGCAGAGGAAGAGCAGCUGCAGAGUUGCAAAGGUCACGAAACUGAGGAGUUUCCAGACGAAGAGCAACUGCGAAGGCGGGAGCUGCUGGAGCUGAGGAGGAAGGGCCGCGAGGAGAAACAGCAGCAAAGGCGAGAGCGGCAAGACAGAGUGUUCCAGGAGGAAGAAGAGAAAGAGUGGAGGAAGCGCGAGACAGUGCUCCGGAAGGAAGAAGAGAAGUUGCAGGAAGAGGAGCCGCAGCGGCAAAGAGAGCUCCAGGAGGAAGAAGAGCAGCUACGGAAGCUGGAGCGGCAAGAGCUGAGGAGGGAGCGCCAGGAGGAAGAGCAGCAGCAGCAAAGGCUGAGGCGCGAGCAGCAACUAAGGCGCAAGCAGGAGGAGGAGAGGCGCGAGCAGCAGGAGGAGAGGCGCGAGCAGCAGGAGAGGCGCGAGCAGCAGGAGGAGAGGCGCGAGCAGCAGCUGAGGCGCGAGCAGGAGGAGAGGCGCGAGCAGCAGCUGAGGCGCGAGCAGGAGGAGGAGAGGCGCGAGCAGCAGCUGAGGCGCGAGCAGGAGGAGGAGAGGCGCGAGCAGCAGCUGAGGCGCGAGCAGCAGCUGAGGCGCGAGCAGCAGCUGAGGCGCGAGCAGCAGCUGAGGCGCGAGCAGCAGCUGAGGCGCGAGCAGCAGCUGAGGCGCGAGCAGCAGCUGAGGCGCGAGCAGCAGCUGAGGCGCGAGCAGCAGCUGAGGCGCGAGCAGGAGGAGGAGAGGCACGAGCAGAAGCACGAGCAGGAGAGGCGCGAGCAGCGGCUGAAGCGCGAGCAGGAGGAGAGGCGCGAUUGGCUGAAGCGCGAGGAGGAGACGGAGAGGCACGAGCAGGAGAGGCGCAAGCAGCAGCUGAAGCGCGACCAGGAGGAGGAGAGGCGCGAACGUUGGCUGAAGCUCGAGGAGGAGGAGAGGCGCGAGCAGCAGGAGAGGCGCGAGCAGCAACUAAGGCGGGAGCAAGAGGAGAGGCGCGAGCAGCGGCUGAAGCGCCAGGAGGAGGAAGAGAGGCUCCAGCAGCGGUUGAGGAGCGAGCAACAACUAAGACGCGAGCAGGAGGAGAGGCGCGAGCAGCUGCUGAAGCGCGAGGAGGAGAAGAGGCUCGAGCAGGAGAGGCGAGAGCAGCGGCUGAAGCGCGAGCAGGAGGAGAGGCGCGAUCAGCUGCUGAAGCGCGAGGAGGAGAGGCGCCAGCAGCGGCUGAAGCGCGAGCAGGAAGAGAGGCUCGAGCAGCGACUGAAGCGCGAGGAGGUGGAGAGACUCGAGCAGGAGGAGAGGCGCGAGCAGCGGCUGAAGCGCGAGGAGCCGGAGGAAGAGAGGCGCCAGCAGCUGCUGAAGAGCGAGGAGCAGGAGGAGAGGCGCCAGCAGCAACUAAGGCGCGAGCAGCAGGAAAGGCGCGAGCAGCGGCUGAAGCGCGAGGAGGAGGAAGAGAGGCUCGAGCAGCGGCUGAAGCGCGAGCAUGAGGAAGAGAGGCGCGAGCAGGAGCUAGCUGAGGAGGAGCAGGAACAGGCCCGGGAGCGGAUUAAGAGCCGCAUCCCGAAGUGGCAGUGGCAGCUAGAAAGCGAGGCCGACGCACGGCAAAGCAAAGUCUACUCGAGGCCCCGCAAGCAGGAAGGGCAGAGGCGCCGCCAAGAGCAGGAGGAAAAGAGGCGGCGCCGGGAGAGUGAGCUGCAAUGGCAGGAGGAGGAACGGGCUCACCGGCAGCAGCAGGAAGAGGAGCAGCGCCGGGACUUCACAUGGCAGUGGCAGGCGGAGGAAAAGAGCGAGAGGGGCCGUCAGAGGCUGUCGGCCAGGCCCCCAUUGCGGGAGCAGCGGGAGAGGCAGCUGAGGGCCGAGGAGCGCCAGCAGCGGGAACAACGGUUUCUCCCGGAGGAGGAGGAGAAGGAGCAGCGGCGCCGCCAGCGACGCGAGAGGGAGAAAGAGCUGCAGUUCCUGGAGGAAGAGGAGCAGCUCCAGCGGCGGGAGCGUGCCCAACAGCUCCAGGAGGAGGAGGACGGCCUCCAGGAGGAUCAGGAGAGGAGGCGAAGCCAGGAGCAGCGCCGCGACCAAAAAUGGAGGUGGCAACUAGAAGAAGAAAGGAAGAGACGCCGCCACACGCUGUACGCCAAGCCAGCCCUACAAGAGCAGCUGAGGAAGGAACAGCAGCUGCUGCAGGAGGAGGAGGAGGAGCUACAGAGAGAGGAGCGCGAGAAGAGAAGGCGCCAAGAACAGGAGAGACAAUACCGCGAGGAAGAGCAGCUGCAGCAGGAGGAAGAGCAGCUGCUGAGAGAGGAACGGGAGAAAAGAAGACGCCAGGAGCGGGAAAGGCAAUAUCGGAAGGAUAAGAAGCUGCAGCAGAAGGAAGAGCAGCUGCUGGGAGAGGAACCGGAGAAGAGAAGGCGCCAGGAGCGGGAGAAAAAAUACCGCGAGGAAGAGGAGUUGCAGCAGGAGGAAGAGCAGCUGCUGAGAGAGGAACGGGAGAAGAGAAGGCGCCAGGAGUGGGAGAGGCAGUACCGCAAAAAAGACGAGCUGCAGCAGGAAGAAGAGCAGCUGCUGAGAGAGGAACGGGAGAAAAGAAGACUCCAGGAGCGGGAGAGGCAAUAUCGGGAGGAAGAGGAGCUGCAGCAGGAGGAAGAGCAGCUGCUGGGAGAGGAACGGGAGACGAGAAGGCGCCAGGAGCUGGAGAGGCAAUAUCGGAAGGAAGAGGAGCUGCAGCAGGAGGAAGAGCAGCUGCUGAGAGAGGAACCGGAGAAGAGAAGGCGCCAGGAGCGGGAGAGGCAAUGUCGGGAGGAAGAGGAGCUGCAGCAGGAGGAAGAGCAGCUGCUGAGAGAGGAACGGGAGAAGAGAAGGCGCCAGGAGCUGGAGAGGCAAUAUCGGGAGGAAGAGGAGGUGCAGCAGGAGGAAGAGCAGCUGCUGAGAGAGGAACCGGAGAAGAGAAGGCGCCAGGAGCUGGAGAGGCAAUACCGCGAGGAAGAGGAGCUGCAGCAGGAGGAAGAGCAGCUGCUGAGAGAGGAACAGGAGAAAAGGCGCCAGGAGCGGGAGAGGCAGUAUCGGGAGGAGGAAGAGCUUCAGCGCCAGAAAAGGAAGCAGCGAUACCGGGAUGAGGAUCAGCGCAGUGAUCUGAAAUGGCAGUGGGAACCAGAAAAAGAAAAUGCAGUUCGUGAUAACAAGGUUUACUGCAAAGGCAGAGAGAAUGAACAGUUCCGGCAGUUGGAAGAUUCCCAGCUGCGCGACAGACAAUCCCAGCAAGAUCUGCAGCACCUGCUGGGUGAACAGCAAGAGCGAGAUCGUGAGCAAGAGAGGAGGCGCUGGCAGCAGCGCGACAGGCAUUUCCCAGAGGAAGAACAGCUGGAGCGAGAAGAGCAAAAGGAAGCCAAAAGGCGCGACAGGAAGUCCCAAGAGGAAAAGCAGUUGCUGAGAGAGGAAAGAGAAGAGAAGAGACGCCGUCAAGAGACAGACAGAAAAUUCCGCGAGGAGGAACAGCUGCUCCAGGAAAGGGAGGAACAGCCGCUGCGCCGCCAAGAGCGUGACAGAAAAUUCCGCGAAGAGGAACUGCGCCAUCAGGAACAAGGGAGAAAAUUCCUCGAGGAGGAACAGCGGCUGCGCCGCCAGGAACGGGAGAGAAAAUUCCUUAAGGAGGAACAGCAGCUGCGCUGCCAGGAGCGCGAGCAACAGCUGCGUCAGGACCGCGACAGAAAAUUCCGCGAGGAGGAACAGCAGCUGAGCCGCCAAGAGCGUGACAGAAAAUUCCGUGAAGAGGAACAGCAGGUGCGCCGCCAGGAACGAGAGAGAAAAUUCCUGGAGGAGGAACAGCAGCUGCGCCAGGAGCGUCACAGAAAAUUCCGCGAAGAGGAACAGCUGCUCCAGGAAAGGGAAGAACAGCAGCUGCACCGCCAAGAGCGUGACAGAAAAUUCCUGGAGGAGGAACAACAGCUGCGCCGCCAAGAGCGUGACAGAAAAUUCCGCGAACAGGAACUGCGCAGUCAGGAACCAGAGAGAAAAUUCCUCGAGGAGGAACAGCAGCUGCACCGCCAGCAACGGCAGAGAAAAUUCCUCCAGGAGGAACAGCAGCUGCGCCGCCAGGAGCGCGGGCAACAGCGGCGUCAGGACCGUGACAGAAAAUUCCGCGAGGAGGAACAGCUGCGCCAGGAGAGGGAGGAACAGCAGCUGAGCCGCCAAGAGCGUGACAGAAAAUUCCGUUUAGAGGAACAGAAAGUGCGCCGCCAGGAACAAGAGAGAAAAUUCAUGGAGGACGAACAGCAGCUGCGCCGCCAGGAGGGCCAACAACAGCUGCGCCAGGAGCGCGACAGAAAAUUCCGCGAAGACGAACAGCUGCUCCAGGAAAGGGAAGAACAGCAGCUGCACCGCCAAGAGCGUGACAGAAAAUUCCUCGAGGAGGAACCGCAGCUGCGCCGCCAGGAGCGCGAACAACAGCUGCGUCACGACCGCGACAGAAAAUUCCGUGAAGAGGAACAGCUGCUCCAGGAAGGGGAGGAACAGCAGCUGCGCCGCCAAGAGCGUGACAGAAAAUUCCGCGAAGAGGAACAGCAGCUCCGCCGUCAGGAACGAGAGAGAAAAUUCCUCCAGGAGGAACAGCAGCUGCGCCGCCAGGAACUGGAGAGAAAAUUCCGUGAGGAGGAACAGCUGCGCCAAGAAACGGAGCAAGAGCAGCUGCGCCGCCAAGAACGCUACAGAAAAAUCCUAGAGGAAGAGCAGCUCCGUCCGGAAAGGGAAGAACAGCAGCUGCGCCGCCAGGAGCGCGACAGAAAAUUCCGCGAGGAGGAACAGCUCCGCCAGGAGAGGGAGGAACAGCAGCUGCGCAGCCAAGAGUCUGACAGAAAAUUCCGCGAGGAGGAACAGCUACGCCAGGAGAGGGAAGAACAGCAGCUGCGCCCCCAACAGCGUGACGGAAAGUAUCGCUGGGAAGAAGAGCAGCUCCAACUUGAGGAACAAGAGCAGAGGCUGCGGCAGGAGCGAGACCGGCAGUACCGGGCGGAGGAGCAGUUUGCCACGCAGGAGAAGAGUCGUCGUGAGGAACAAGAACUAUGGCAAGAAGAGGAGCAGAAACGUCGCCAGGAACGGGAAAGGAAAUUACGGGAAGAACACAUCCGCCGCCAGCAGAAGGAGGAACAGAGGCACCGCCAAGUCGGGGAGAUAAAAUCCCAAGAAGGGAAGGGCCAUGGGCGGCUUCUGGAGCCCGGCACUCAUCAGUUUGCCAGUGUCCCAGUGCGCUCCAGCCCUCUCUAUGAGUACAUCCAAGAGCAGAGAUCUCAAUACCGCCCUUAAGUGAUGUUGCCAAUAUCUUGACACCUGCCAAAGCUUCGAGCACGGGAAAAUGAGAAACACUGGGUACCAAGUGAUAACUCAGAUGUUUCUGGUUGUGGGAAAACUCUCUGAUAUUAGAAUGUCUUUUCUUCCAAAAUCUUAAACUACGCUCAUUUUACGCACUUUGUACUUCUGCUUUUUAUUCUUCCUCAAGUAGUUCUUUACUGCAAGAUGUCUUUCUUUUGCUCUUUGAUGCAGAUGUGGUGUGCAUUUAAAAAAAAUAUAAAUCAUUUAAUUUGUUUAAGAAAUUUUGUUUGAGGAACAUGUUCAUUUAUUGCUUUCAGAAGUAACAAGAGUAAUAGGAUGAUUUGAGAUUCUAAACAAUGGGUCGGUUUGUUUAAUGACUGACCCAUCUUGUGGAAAGUGCAGAUACUUUUAAUGUUCAAGUUGCUAUUUCUUCUUGAACCUAAAUUGAUCAUUGCCUCCAAACAGCAUUUCAUCUUUUGUGGCAUAGUUAGCACAAAUUCCAGGUAACUAAAUUUUUAUAACCCUUGAAUAGUGCAGGGGGAGUGACCUCUGCAUAAAAACUUCCUGUAAAAUCAGCCCAUUACUGGAAGAAAUAUCUGUUAAGAAUAGGUUUAGCUUUGAAGAUUUAGAAUUUAAAUUAGAUUUUUUUUAAACUCAACUCCACUUAAACACAUAAUCUCAUGAAGAAAUAAUGAGGUGUUUCUCAACUUCAGAGUUCAAAUUUUAAAACUGUGUCUGUUGUAGUCUAUAGUGUUCAUUCUACUUCCCCAAGUUUUGAUGAGUUUCAGAAUAUUAUGAACCUUUGUUAAUUUUAGCUUGUUAGAAGGAAGCUGCUCAGAAUCCCAUAAACAUCUGUCUUACUCUAGGGCCAAUAAGAGAUCACAUAGAGCAUGUUGGGGGUGUAAAAGGGAAAAAUGUGUGAACAUAGGGGCAAAUUUCUAGAGGCCCUUUGACAAGACCCAUUUGCCCACAAUCAUUUGAGGCCUAUUGAUAAUACCUUAGAUAUAUUCUUGUUGAAAUAAUUGGACUGUGAAAAAUUAAUAAUAAAUGUUUGGCAAGUAA